AUUGGAAAAACUGGUUAUUUUACCAAGGCUUUGACUGGAAUGGUGUGCUUUCCUUUAAGGAAUCAAACUUAACUUAUGAAGCCAAUAAAGCCCUUGGAAAACUAACCUCAUAUUUUGUCUACAGAGUCCCUGUACAGGGUUUCUGAUCCAUGACUCCCAAAAGCCAGGCUGCCGAGGCCACCAAAGUGGCUAUUGACGUAGGCUUCCGCCAUAUUGAUUCAGCAUACUUAUACCAAAAUGAGGAGGAGGUUGGACAGGCCAUUUGGGAGAAGAUCGCUGAUGGUACCGUCAAGAGAGAGGAAAUAUUCUACACCAUCAAGCUUUGGGCUACUUUCUUUCGGGCAGAAUUGGUUCACCCGGCCCUAGAAAGGUCACUGAAGAAACUUGGACCGGACUAUGUAGAUCUCUUCAUUAUUCAUGUACCAUUUGCUAUGAAGGUCAGCUUUUGUUUUUCCUUGUUAUGCCCAAGACUGUUUCAUCAUGGUUAUAAGCAUCUGAAUUAUCUAAUUCUAGCUUGGUUUCCAGGGUUCUUCCUGAGAGAGGCAGAUUUGAGUGAGGUGCAUAGGAUUGCCAAAACUUUCCCUGGGAAAGAAUUACUGCCAAAGGAUGCCAGUGGAGAGAUUAUUUUAGAAACUGUGGAGCUUUGUGACACUUGGGAGGCCCUGGAGAAGUGCAAAGAAGCAGGUUUAACCAGGUCCAUUGGGGUGUCCAAUUUCAAUCACAAGCUGCUGGAACUCAUCCUCAACAAGCCAGGGCUCAAGUACAAGCCCACCUGCAACCAGGUGGAAUGUCACCCUUACCUCAACCAGAGCAAACUCCUGGAGUUCUGCAAGUCCAAGGACAUUGUUCUAGUUGCCUACAGUGCCCUGGGAUCCCAAAGAGACCCACAGUGGGUGGAUCCCGACUGCCCACAUCUCUUGGAGGAGCCGAUCUUGAAAUCCAUUGCCAAGAAACACAGUGGAAGCCCAGGCCAGGUCGCCCUGCGCUACCAGCUGCAGCGGGGAGUGGUGGUGCUGGCCAAGAGCUUCUCUCAGGAGAGAAUCAAAGAGAACUUCCAGAUUUUUGACUUUGAGUUGACUCCAGAGGACAUGAAAGCCAUUGAUGGCCUCAACAGAAAUCUCCGAUAUGACAAGUUACAAUUGCUUUGGUAUCAGGAUGAUGCUGGCCUCUGUCUUCUGCAUCAAUCACGCUGGGAGCUGCAGAUGGGAGCUGUUCAUAUUCAGCCAUCUUGGAAUGGACUCCCAGUGAGGGAAUAGUUUCUAGCAGCCAAAAGAUUACAUCCUGCUGAAGGAUUACAACAUCAUCAGGACUGCAUUUUCAUCAGGAAUGAAUAUUCCUUCUACAAUGCAAAGAAAAAAAACCCAAAAUAUUUGCUGAUGGAAAGGUGGAAUGUCAUCCUUACCUCAACCAGAGCAAACUGCUGGAUUUCUGCAAGUCAAAAGACAUUGUUCUGGUUGCCCACAGUGCUCUGGGAACCCAACGACAUGAACUAUGGGUGGACCAGAACUCACCAGUUCUUUUGGAGGACCCAGUUAUUUGUGUCAUGGCAAAAAUGCACAAGUGAUCCCCAGCCCUGAUUGCUCUGUGCUACCAGCUGCAGCGUGGGGCUGUGGUCCUGGUCAAGAGCUCCAAUGAACAGCAGAUCAGAGAGAACAUGCAGGUGAGGCGUUGGGUGGGCAUUAGGACUCCUGCAUGGUGUCCUUCACACAUGUGCUUCCUGUAAGGUGAGAACAGGAUACUGUUGGACUAAGUCCAUUUCCUGGUUAUUUCCUAUGCACAAAUGCUUUCUGUACAUCCUAAAGGUUUUCUACUCUACCACAGAAGAGGCAGCAUGGGUGGAGAGAAUUAGGAUGGAACCAAAACCAGAGAUUUGGGUUUCAACAUUAAGUUGGCAAUUUAUUAUGCAUUCCUGUGCUAGCGACAUCUGCUUUUCUUGAUUUUCUGAAAUGAGGAGUUGGAUUAGGUGUUCUCUAGUCUCCAAAUCAUUGCUGAUUUUUUUCAUUUCCUUCUUUACUCAGUAUGAAUUUCAUAUAUUCUCUUAGAGUUUUCUUUAUAGUAGUACCUGUUAAAGUCUUUGGGUAUUUUUAUUAGUUUGCUUGUCUCUUUCUAUGUGUAGAACACCAUAAUUAUACUAAUAUGUUUGCCCCAGAAAAAGCAUUUCCUGAUCAACUGUUCUACUUGCUCACCUCAUGACCCCUGAAUACUGUCUAUUUGCAGCUGUGUUUGCUUGUCGUUAUAAAAAAUGUUUUCUGACUGAUCUUUGAGACACAUAGAUGUUAUGCUCAGAGUCCUACCCUUUGAAUAAAUUUCUCUUGCUUAAGUCUAGGUUGGUUUCUUGAAUGGGAUUGUUCCGUGUUUUAAGGGUUGCUCAGUCUAAGGCUGGAUCAAGUUCCCGGGGAAGUGGGGAAACAAGAGCCUGACCAAGUGUGGUCAAGUCCAGGUGGCAGGUAUUGUGUCUACACUUUCUUUUCCAUUUUAAAACAAGUGAUUUCCUUUUUCUGUCUCAAGCAAUUUUCUAGAAAUAUUUUAGAUUGAUGAGUGCACAUCUUUCUUUUGAGAAGUGGUGCAGAAUAGAAGAGGGGUGGGAUGGAGAAGAGGCAGAGCUCAGGUGGAAGAGGUCCCAGGCCAGGUGCACCUGGAAGCCGAUGAGGAUAGAAAUGCCUCCCCUAAUGCCAUCCUUGCCUUUGCCCCUUGCAAAGUCCUUGGAUUCCCAGGUAGAAGCUGCUGUCCUGGGAAAGGUGAAUGUGAGUAUCGCCUGCCUUUCAGGUUUUUGACUUUGAGUUGACUCCAGAGGACAUGAAAGCCAUUGACAGCCUCAACGGAAAUCUCCGACAUGCUAAGUUACAAUUUUAAGUGAUGCAGAUUCUUUCACAGACCAUUUUCUGCAGGAUGCACAAAAACAGAGGGACACAUCUUUCCUACAUCAGGAAGACAGGCCUGAAUUCAGGCAUGGGGUGAAACAGGAGAUUCACUGUAGCCCUCAGACCAUAGGUUUCCUCCACGGCUCAAUUUCUGACCCAACAGGAAUGUUGGUCUGUAAGUAACACUGCCUAUGUCUGCACCAUUGUGAAUCACUUUUUUUGAUGCCCUCACUACCUGUGCCUGGGUCCUACGCUUUGGACGCUCUUACCCAUUAGACUAGAAGGCACAGGGCUGUCUUAAUUUAUGCUAAAAAAAGAAAAAUUAAUAUGAUAACAAAUAUGUAAUAAUGACUCAAACCUGGUCCCUCUUUGUGUCUCCACCGAGGCAACGUAAGACAUAAUUUUAAUAUUUUUAUGGAGAUGGGCCCAGGUAGGUAAAUGUGCGUAGGUCCUAGGGAAGUCACAGUGGGCCCUGCUUCCAUGUCCUCCCGUAAGAGUCCAGUGGCAUUUCUCCUUAAUGUGGCAUUACCUUUUCAGGACACCAUUUAUAUCUCCCAAAUUUAUGUCUUCCUUGGCUUUCUUCGCCUGUCACAACUCUCAUUUUCUCAGCUCUAUAAAUCUCACCAACCUGAAUGAUAAAUGAAUUAUGAAAUUAAUAGACCCUCAGUGCUAGUGACUGAGGUGUCCCCUAUGGCCUCUACCAAGAUAAGAUCCUCUGGAGUUUCUCUGGAUCCUCAGGGCAAGACUCUUACUCCAGUGUCAUCUUUGUCCAUCUGAAGCCCAUCUCUGGGGAACCCAACAUCCCUUAACUUUGGUUUGUUCACAAACAUGACGUUCCAUUGGAUUAACUGUGGCAGGAUCUCAGGAUUGAGGAGAAAGAAGAGGAAUCAAACACAAAGAAGUUUGGAGGGGAGUGUAGAAAUAGGGAAAAAAUGAAAUUUUUUAUGUGUGUUUGCACCCGACAGAGAUUUUAUAUGCAAAAAUCAAAAAAAGAAAAGCCUCUAUGUCGUUUUAUGCUUCACUUAAAAAAAAACCUGGAUUGUUGUAGAGCAUAUUAACUUAAAAUUCUAUUUAUAAUCCCUUGAUUCAUUAUAUUACUUAUACAUUACAUAUAUAAUAUCAUAAUUAGCAUGGCUUGGAAAUAUAUGCUCAUUUUGCUGCUUAGCAAUGUAAUAGCAUCAUAUUUUCCACUUCUACACUCCAAACUGGUAGAAUAAUUACCAAAAACUAAAAUAAAAUAAAAAUAUGACUAUUUCAGAAAUAGGGAAAAAAUUUUAAUUAUGAGAAUAGAGAUUCAGUCCCCCCCAAAAAUAUGUGAACAGUCUCUCUUCUUUUUGUGAAACCAUACCAGGAUUCUGAGAGAAGACAUUUUUGAACGAACAAAAAUGUGGGAAGUGACUUUUACAUACUGAAAGGCUUUAAGUAGAAAUCUGUGGCCUCCCUCAUGAGAGUGUUUAGACUUGUCUUACUCAUCUCUGUGACCCUAUUCAAUAUCACAGCUCCUGGCACACUAACUACUGAAAAGGUACUCAUUAUUCACAUUCAGUUGGAAAGGACAAAUUAUAAAAAUGAAAAAAAAGAACACGGGAAAA